AGUGUUCGGCUGGGGCAGGCACGCUGUGGCUGGCUACUUCCCUUCCUCCCAUCCCCCUUGGGCCAAACGGGAUCGGUGCUUCUGGAAACAAUGACCGAUAAAACAGAGAAGGUGGCUGUAGAUCCUGAAACUGUGUUUAAACGUCCCAGGGAAUGUGACAGUCCUUCGUAUCAGAAAAGGCAGAGGAUGGCCCUGUUGGCAAGGAAACAAGGAGCAGGAGACAGCCUUAUUGCAGGCUCUGCCAUGUCCAAAGAAAAGAAGCUUAUGACAGGACAUGCUAUUCCACCCAGCCAAUUGGAUUCUCAGAUUGAUGACUUCACUGGUUUCAGCAAAGAUAGGAUGAUGCAGAAACCUGGUAGCAAUGCACCUGUGGGAGGAAACGUUACCAGCAGUUUCUCUGGAGAUGACCUAGAAUGCAGAGAAACAGCCUCCUCUCCCAAAAGCCAACGAGAAAUUAAUGCUGAUAUAAAACGUAAAUUAGUGAAGGAACUCCGAUGCGUUGGACAAAAAUAUGAAAAAAUCUUCGAAAUGCUUGAAGGAGUGCAAGGACCUACUGCAGUCAGGAAGCGAUUUUUUGAAUCCAUCAUCAAGGAAGCAGCAAGAUGUAUGAGACGAGACUUUGUUAAGCACCUUAAGAAGAAACUGAAACGUAUGAUUUGAGAAUACUUGUCCCUGGAGGAUUAUCACACCCCAAAUGCAUAAUCUCGUUAAUGAUUGAGGAGAGAAAAGGAUCAGAUUGCUGUUUUCUACAAUGGAGCAGGAUAUUGCUGAAGUCUCCUGGCAUAUGUUACCGAAUCAAAUAGCCUUCCAGAGGCUAAGAAAUUUCUGUUAGUAAAAGAUGUUCUUUUUCCCAAAGCAUUUUAUUUGAAAGGAUAACUUGUGUUUUGGUUAUUUUGUAUUCCCACCUGUGCUGGUAGAUAUUAUUAACCCAUUAGGUAAAUACUAUUACAGUCGUGGUUUCUGCAGCA